GACUUCAGUAAAGGGAACCCGGGGCUCUCGCAGCCAGCCCUCCUGCCCAUGGAGGACAGUUUCCUUCAAUCUUUUGGGAGGCUGAGCCUCCAGCCCCAGCAGCAGCAGCAGCGGCAGCGGCCGCCCCGGCCGCCCCCGCGGGGGACACCUCCUCGCCGCCACAGCUUUAGGAAACACCUCUACCUCCUGCGAGGCCUCCCGGGCUCCGGGAAAACUACACUGGCCAGGUGAAAAUGUUUGAUGUGCCGGCUCCUUUACCUCAUAGUUACAGUAAGAAGAAAUUUAAAAAUUGGGAUCAAAGAUGCAGCCGCCUUCCCAUUUAAGCAGCACAGACAGCCCAAAGUGACAGUUUUCCUGUACAGUUACUCUUCUGUUAUCUGUAACUGAUCUAUGACAUUUUGGGAAAAAACAGCCAAAAAAAAUUAGUACUGAGGUAGGUGUGCCUGAUUCCUUCCCCAAUUCUGCUCAUGACUGAACCAACAGAACACAAACACAGGUGAAACCUGCACAGCUGUGAGAGCCUACAAAAGUUCACAUGCAAGAUACUUAAAGGAAUUUCUGCUCAAUAGAGUCUGUGGGACCACACUGACAAACGAGAAUGAGGGCUCUCUGGGAGCCUGGCUUUGGACCUCAUGAACAUGGUCUACUUUGGAGGUAUGAGGGGUAAAGGUAAGAGAAGUAGGGCAGACUGGGAACUGUUCCCUGAGUCCCCCUAGCCACUGUGGCUUGGGGACACUUGAGGCUAGCAGUGAUUGAGGCUUGGCUCUCCAAGGACAGGACUUGGCCCUGGUGGGGUGGGUGGCAGCACUGCCCAGGUUCGGCCACACCUGGCCUCAGGGGAGGCUGCCCAUGUCAUCUAUAGCUUGGCUCCCUCCCUGCUCUCAGGCUGCUGAGCCAUGGAAUCUGUUUUCUAUCUCCCAGUUUAAAGUCCUCAAGAAGAAUGUCAGUAGCAUUCAGAGGAAGUGCUGGGAUCCAGGAAGAAUCCUCUCCGUCAGUCUCCUUUAAGGGUUGUAUUAGUCUGUUCUCAUUCUACUAAUAAAGACAUACCCAAAACUGGAUAAUUUAUAAAGGAAAGAGGUUUAAUUGACUCACAGUUCAGCAUGGCCGGGGAGGCCUCAGGAAACAACUUACAAUCGUGGUGGAAGGGGAAGCAAACAUGUCCUUCUUCACAUGGCGGCAGGAAGGAGAAGUGCUGAGCAAAAGGGGGAAAAGCCUUAUGAAACCAUCAGAUCAGCCGGGCGCAGUGGCUUAUGCCUGUAAUCCCAGCACUUUGGGAGGCCAAGGCAGGCAGAUCACCUGAAGUCAGGAGUUCAAGACCAGCCUAGCCAACAUAGUGAAACCCCGUCUGUAAAAUACAAAAAAAAAAAAAAAAAAAAAAAAAAAAAAAAAAAUUAGCCAAGCAUGGUGGCAAGCACCCGUAAUCCUGGCUAGUCAAGAGGCUGAGGCAGGAGAAUCACUUGAACCCGAGAGAUGUAGGUUGCAGUGAGCUUAGAUUGUGCCACUGCACUCCAGCCUGGGUGAUCGAGCAAGACUCUGUCUCAAAAAAAAAAAAAAAAAAAAAAAAGCCAGAUCUUGUGAGAACUCACUAUCAUGAGAACAGCAUGAGGGUAACUGCUCCCAUGAUUCAGUUACCUCCCAUCGGAGGUAAUUCCCAUGACGUGGGGAUUAUGGGAACUAUAAUUCAAGAUGAGAUUUGGGUGGGGACUGCCCCUGGCUCCUCCAAAAUCUCAUGUCCUCACAUUUCAAAACACAAUCAUGUCUUCCUAACAGUCCCCCAAAGUCUUAACUCAUUCCAGCAUUAACUCAAAAGUCCAAGUCCAAAGUCUCAUCUGAGACAAGGCAAGUCCCUUCUGCUUAUGAACCUGUAAAAUCAAAAGCAAGUUGGUUACUUCCUAGAUACAAUGGGGGUACAGGCAUUGGGUAAAUACACCUAUUCCAAAUGGAAGAAAUUGGCCAAAACAAAAAGGCUAUAGGCCCCAUGCAAGCCCAAAAUCCAGCAGGGUAGCCAAAUCUUAAAGCUCCAAAAUGAUCUCCUUUGACUCCAUGUCUCAUAUCCAGGUCAUGCUGAUGCAAGAGGUGGGCUCCCAUGGCCUUGGGCAGCUCCACCCCUGUGGCUUUGCAAGGUACAGCUCCACUCCUGGCUGCUUUCACAAGCUGGCAUUGAGUGUCUGCGGCUUUUCCAGGCACAAGCUGCAAGCUGUCAGUGGAUCUACCAUUCUGGGGUCUGGUGGGCAGUGGCCCUCUUCUUACAGCUCCACUAGGCAGUGCCCCAGUGGAGCCUCUGUGUGGGGGCUUUGACCCCACAUUUCCCAUCUGCACUGCACUAGCAGAGAUUCUCCAUGAGGGCACCACCCCUGCAGCACACCUCUGCCUGGAAAUCCAGGCAUUUCCAUACAUCUUCUGAAAUCUAAGUGGAGGUUCCCAAACCUCAGUUAUUGACUUCUGUGCACCCACAGGCCCAACACCAUGUGGCAGCUGCCAAGGCUUGGGGCUUGUACCCCCUGAAGCAAUGGUCUGAGCUGUACAUUGACCCCUUUUAGCCAUGGCCAGCCAGAGCUGCUGGGAAGCAGGGCACAAAGUUUCAAGGCUGCACACAGCAGGGGGGCCCAGGACCCAUCUCAUGAAACCAUUUUUCCCUCCUAGGUCUCCAGGCCUGUGAUGGGAGAGGCUGCCAUGAAGUCCUCUGCCAUGCCCUGGAGACAUUUUCCCCAUUGUCUUGGUGAUUAACAUUUGGCUCCUCGUUACUUAGGCAAAUUUCUGCAGCUGGCUUGAAUUUCUCACCUGAAAAUGGGGCUUUCUUUUCUAUCACAUCAUCAGGCUGCAAAUUUUCCAAACUUUUGUGCUCUGCUUCCUCUUGAAUGCUUUGCUGCUUAGAAAUUUCUUCAACCAGAUACCCUAAAUUGUUUCUUUCAAGUUCAAAGUUCCACAUGUGGAUCUCUAGGGCGGGGCAAAAUGCCACCAGUCUCUUUGCAUAGCAAGAGUGACCUUUACUCCAGUUCCCAGUAAGUUCCUCAUCUCUGAGACCACCUCAGCCUGGACUUCAUCGUCCAUAGCAGCAUUUUGGUCAAAGCCAUUCAACAAAUCUCUAGGAAGUUCCAAACUUACCCACAUAUUCCUGUCUUCUGAGCCCUUCCAUUAGUUCCAGUCUCUGCCUGUUACCCAGUUCCAAAGUUGCUUUCACAUCUUUGGGUAUCUUUACAGCAGUGCCCCAUUCUCUGUGGUACCAAUUUGCCGUUCUCACACUGCUAAUAAAGACAUACCCGAAACUGGGUAAUUUAUAAAGGAAAGAGGUUUAAUUGACUCACAGUUCAGCAUGGCUGGGGAGGCCUCAGGAAACUUAUAAUCAUGGUGGAAGGGGAAGCAAACACAUCCUCACAUGGUGACAGCAAGGAGAAGUGCUGAGCAAAAGGGGAAAAAGCCCCUUAUAAAACCAUCAGAUCUUGUGAGAACCCACUAUCAUGAGAACAGCAUGAGGGUAACCAUUGCCAUGAUUCAAUUACCUCCCACUAGGUCCCUCCCAUGACACAUGGGGAUUAUGGGAACUACAAUUAAAGAUGAGAUUUGAGUGGGGACACAGCCAAACCAUAUUGAGGACGAACUGAAUCUAAGGUUUGGGUAAAAUUCUCAUUGUACAAAAAUGAGUAAAUAGAAAUUCUCACACAGCUUGGGACUCUAUAAAAAAGUUUGCCAGCUGGGCCUGGUGGCUCAAGCCUGUAAUCCCAGUACUUUGGGAGGCCAAGGCGGGUGGAUCAUGAGGUCAGGAGUUCGAGACCAGCCUGGCCGAGAUGGGGAAACCUCGUCUCUACUAAAAAUACAAAAAUUAGCCAGGGGUGGUGGCACGCGCCUGUAAUCCCAGCUACUCGGGAGGCUGAGGCAGGAGAAUUGCUUGAACCCAGGAGACAGAGAUUGCAGUGAGCCGAGAUCAUGCCAUUGCACUUCAGCCUGGGCGACAGAGCAAGACUCCGUCUGGAGGGGGGUGGGGCGGGGAACAAAAAAAAAAGAGUUCGCAUAAUUAGGCUAAAAGAGCGUCGUAUUCAGGAGCCAUUAAUACAUUCACAGAUAUUUACUGAGCAUCUCCCAUGUGCCUGGCAUUCUUCUAGAUGCUCAGAAUGGAGCAGUGGACAAAGGAGACAAAAAUCCCUGCCUUCAUGGAACAUGUAUUCUAUCAGAGAAAAAAAAUUCUCAAGGAAAAAAGGCAAUUUUAGCAUCUGCUCUGCUCUGUUCUCUCAAAAAAUAAGCAAAGGAUUUCACAGGUAUGCCACCGGAGGUAUAUAUCCCCAGGAAAUGUCCACAUACACACAAGAGUGUUCUAGGUACUUGGGAAUCAUCAGUGAACAAAACAAAGAUCCUGCCCUUGUGGACCUUAUGUGCCAGAGACAAUUGCAGCAUGACUUUCCCAGGGCCCUGAUUUUCAGCACGGAUGAUUUUUUCUUCAGGGAAGAUGGUGCCUAUGAGUUCAAUCCUGACUUCCUGGAGGAAGCUCAUGAAUGGAACCAAAAAAGAGCAAGAAAAGCAAUGAGGAAUGGCAUAUCCCCCAUUAUUAUUGAUAAUACCAACCUCCACGCCUGGGAAAUGAAGCCCUAUGCAGUCAUGGCACUUGAAAAUAACUAUGAAGUUAUAUUCCGAGAACCUGACACUCGCUGGAAAUUCAACGUUCAAGAGUUAGCAAGAAGAAACAUUCAUGGUGUCUCAAGAGAAAAAAUCCACCGAAUGAAAGAACGGUAUGAACACGAUGUUACUUUUCACAGUGUGCUUCAUGCAGAAAAGCCAAGCAGAAUGAACAGAAACCAGGACAGGAAUAAUGCAUUGCCUUCCAACAAUGCCAGAUACUGGAAUUCCUACACAGAGUUUCCAAACCGGAGGGCCCACGGUGGAUUUACAAAUGAGAGCUCCUAUCACAGAAGGGGCGGUUGUCACCAUGGAUAUUAGAGGCCUAUCUUACAGCCAGGCAGAAUUUUCCUAAGUCAGUUUCUACUUCAGUUUUUGUUAUUUUUUGUUGCAUUUUAGUCAGAGCUCCAAUUCCAGUGUAAAUAGCUGAACUCAAAAGUUUCUGAGCAAAGUCAUUAUAUUCACUUUCUUCACCAAAAUUUGUUAAAGUGCUUCUAUAUGCAUGGUCUGAUGCUGGGAAUUCUGCAGAUUUGAGUAAACAGUCUCUUUCUCUAGGGUAAGAAUUUGAAACCAAAACUUGAGAACACACCCAAGAAUAUAUUUACAUAGGUUCAUAGAUGAAAUAAAGUGUUUAUAUUAUAUAUAAGCUUCAGUACCAUUUGCUCUGAAGUGAUCUAUUUAUUUUUUCAGGAAAUUCAUCUCCAUCGGUAAAGUUGGGAAGGUGGAGAGAAGUGGUGGGGGGGCAUUGCUACUUAUCAAAGUGCCAUUGCUACUUUGAUAAUCUAUGUAUCUAAAAAUGUGAGAUGUGCGACUCUUAUGAUACUGAUUUUCCUUUAAUGUUAAUAUGCCAGAAAGCAUACAUCUAAGGGAACAUUGUCCUUCAAAGUAGACACUUUGGGAAGUUAUUUCUUUAUUUUAAUGAUGUAUCAUUGUUAAAAAUGCUGUCAAAUCCUUAAUAGCUACAGGAGCUACUGAGGGAAAUCAGUGUCAUUAUUUAAAGUCACGCCUUGUGUUUUUACUACUUUAUUCAGCAGGAUUAAACCUGAAUAACUUUUGGCUGUUGUGCUAAUAGUGUAAAUAAAAUAAGCCUGCCUUCAUAAAACACUAACUUUUAAAAGGAAUAAACGACUUCUAAAAUUAUGCCUAUUAACAUGUGUAAUUAGUCGGCAGCUCAAAUGUUUGGGAGUGCAAGAAAUUAGGCACCCCAGGAUAUAGGUCAUACAGGGAUAUAUAAAAGCCAUGCUCAUUACAAAAUGAGCAGUUGAUGUUUUAUGUGGCAUUAAGACAAUCAAGUCCUCACAACUCUGGAAUGUCUUCUUAUACUGAUGCUGAAUUUAUGAAUCCAAAUUAAUUUCCAACAGGUUGGAAUCAGAUUUAAUGUGAGAUCAUGAUAGACAAGACCACAGAGGACGUAUGCUCUAUUUCUUGUUGGCCAACAGCUUCUUUCUAAUGUUCUGUGAAAAAUUAUUUUAAGUGUCUUAUAUAAUGGUGCUUUUAUGGUUAUUAAAAAUUGUAAAUGGUAUCACAUUUAUAUGGAUUUGUCAUUGGAUCUUUUUUUGGUUCAACAAUAAAAAAAUUUAAUUACCUAAAUGCCAAGAAACUCAACAAUAUACCAGUUUUUCUGUAUCACAGGCUUAUUUACCAGUCUUUUUUUUAAUAAAUAGGAAUCGUAAAGGUAAUGACAAAAGCAGCCUUAUAAUUUAGUUGCUUAUAUAUUUGAUCUGUGUACAUGAGACUGUUUUAACGUUAUCUGACACUACUGAAACCUGCUCGACAUCUCCAUGACUACCAACACCAUGUGUAAUGUUUUCUUCACUAACAUUUUAAAAACUGGUAUCUCCUUUGAGUAAGUUUGGCUGACAAUAGUAAAUCCCAAUGAAUCUAAGGUGUUAUCAGCUUUGCUAACUUCUGUAUCUCCAAGCACAACAUAAAAUAAUCUCCUAAUGAUCUACUUAAUAAUGCUCCCAUUUUCCAGGCCCAGGUAGUCCUGGGUAUCUUGGUUGAUAGGGUGGUGGCAUAACCAGCUCAAUAUGGAUGGCUUGACUCGUCUGGGCUGGUAGAGGGGAGAAAUGUCAGAGAGCUCAAAGUGGAAAUUACCAUCCUUUGAUUUCACAUGAGCGGUUCAAAGGACCAGAUUCAAGCCCUCCUGACUUGGCUGGCUCCCUGCUUUAGGGUUUUUGGCUCACUUGGGUUAAGUGAGUGACCACUAUGGAGAAGUGGCUCUGGGUUACAUAACUUUUCUAGAGCUCUAAAGAAUAGUUUCCUGGCCUAUUUAAUGUCUCUUCUUUCCCUAGCUGACCCCUGAAAUAUUUGGUUUGUAAACCAUAAAAAUUGAUUAAAUGCCAUCAACUUUAUCCCCUGUAGAAGUGAUCUGUUUUUCAACUCCCAUGGCUUCUGAUUUGUGUAACUCUUUGAACACCCAAUAUUGACUUGUAUUGUGUUCGCUGUUUGCAUCAUUCAUAGAACUGGCAAAUGCUCUUUAUGGGCAAUAGGGUCUCAUUAAAUGAUUGCUGAAUAAAUAACACAAAUUUUUACCAUUA